CUCCAGCCCAGGCAACAGAGCGUGACUCCGUCUCAAAAAAAAAAAAAAAAGUGAAAGGAAAAUGAGGGGAGAAUUCUCAUUGAUAAUAAGGGCGAAAAGGUUUUUUUGGCAGAGUAAUAGAGUUUUGGAAACCAUUGCAAAGCUGUCAAGUGUGGUGUAGUUUUUGGUUAAGGAAAUCAGAGGUGUCAGCAGACAUAAAAGACAGGGGAAAACAUGGGAAGUGUCCUACCUAUAGUGUAGAAAAAGCACAACUAUCUAUGUCAGAGGUCGACAGACUGUGGUCCAUAGGUCAAAUCUGGCCCACGAUCUGUUUUUGUAAAUAACGUUUUAUUGGAACAUAGCCACACUCAUUUAUUUAUAUAUUGUCCAUAUCUUCUUUUGUGGUACCAAUAGCAGAGUUGAGUAGUCGUGACAGAGAUGUGUUGUGUCAGCUCACAAAGCUGGAAAUACUCUUUACAAAAACAUUUGCCAACCCCUGAUCUAUGUGUUUGAGUGUUGGAUGUUCAACCUCUAAUUUGCCAUCCAAUGUCUAUAUGAUGAUAGAGAAUGAAUAAACGUCUUGGCUCUGCCCUUUGGGCUGGAUUACCCAUGCUCUGUGUACCUGCAGCAUAACACAGACCCCUGAAUAUUUAUAUCAGUCAGUGAUGGCAAGGUCUAUUGUUCUGGAGUGUACUGUGUGGUAACUGUGGUAGUGCCAGCUUUACACGGAUUAGAUAAUGCUCGGGCUUGUUUUGCCAUUUUUUUUAUUGGGUUGUCUUUUACAAAAGAUUUAUUUAUAUAUUCUGAUUAUUAAUCCUUUGUUGUUGGUAGAUAUUACAGAUGUCAUUUCCCAGUUUCUUGCUUAUUUUAAUUUUUUUUUUUUUUUUUUUGAGAUGAAGUCUUGCUCUGUCGCCCAGGCUGGAGUGCAGUCGUGCCAUCUCAGCUCAUUGUAACCUCCGUCUCCCAGGUUCAAGUGAUUCUCUUGCCUCAGCCUCCCAAGUAGCUGGGACUACAGGCAUGUGCCACCACACCUGGCUGAUUUUUGUGUUUUUAGUAGGGAUGGGGUUUCAUCAUGUUGGCCAGGCUGGUCUCAAACUCCUGACCUCAAGUGAUCCACCCGUCUUGGCCUCCUAAAGUGCUGGGAUUACAGGUGUGAGCCACUGCGCCUGGCCUGUUGCUUAUUUUAAAACAUCUGUUUUAAGGUGUCAUUUGUUAAAAAGUUCUGAAUUUUAGUAUCAACUUUAUCAAUCUUUUCCUUUAAGAUUUGCAGUUAUUCUUUGUUUUGAGGCAGGGUCUCGCUCUGUCACCGAGGCUGGAGUGCAGUGGUGCGAUCUCGGCUCACUGCAGCCUCAACCUCCUGGGCUCAAGCAACCCUCCCACCUCCCAUGCCAGUUGAGACCACAGGCAUGCGCCACCAUGCCCUGCUACUUUUUGCAUUUUUUGUAGAGGCGGGGUUUCGCCAUGUUGCCCAGGCUAGUCUGGAACUCCUGAGCUCAAGCAGUCCACAAAGUGCUGGGAUUACAGGUGUGAGCUACUGUGCCCAGCCUGCAAUUAUUCUUUAUAUUCUGGAAUACCUACUGUUGUUUUCAAUGGUUAGAUCUUUAAUGUAUCUGGAAUGGAUUCUUAUGUGUAGUGUAAGGUCGGGUCCAGUUUCAUUUUUUUUCCCUAUGUAUAACCAGUGAUCCCAGCAUCAUUUAUUGAAUGGGGCUUGCUUUCAAAUUGUGAGCUCUUUUUGGUGGAGUCUGUCUCAGGUCCUUAUUAAGCACUGCUGCUUGCUGAUUGUGUGACCUUGGACAAAUAAAACCUCAUUGCGCCUCAGUCUUUAAGGAUAAUAGUAAUCUCAUAGGGUUUUGUGAGGAUUAAAUGAGUCAAUAUACAUAACGUGUAAAACAGUGCUUGGCACCUAGAACAUGCUCAAUAAAUAUUAGCUGUACUUUAGCACUACUGUUCAUUUCUGAUUCCUCAGCACCUGGUACAGAGCAGGGGCUCAUUUUGCUCAAUUAAAUUGCCAAAUUAAUUUGGUUUUCAGGUCAAUCAGAAUGGUGAGAGUUGGGCUGAGUGUUGCAGGAGAUGCUUCCAAGGAGCUACUUAGUUUUAGGGGCUGCCUUAGAUUAUCUGCUAGGAUAGAACUCUUCUCACGCCAUCACUUUUGCAGAGAACUUCUGUAGCAGAGGUUGCAAACUGGCAACCUGUGGUUGGAUUUGACCUGUAUAAGUAUUUUGUUUGGUUUACACAAUAUUUUUAAUGUCUUAAAAAUGUACACAGACCUCUGAGUUUCUGACUUAACCUUGAAAAAUUGGAAGAUCUGUCAACAGCAAGCCCAUAUUCAUUUAUAGCGGUAACCAGCUGAAACUUUUAGGUCCUGGGAGGAAUGGAGAGGGGUCCCACUGACUAACUUUUCUGAGAGUGGUCAGAGAGUUCUUAAGCAGAAUUUUGAUUUGGCUGCUGGGCUGCUACCUUGAAAUCCAAGCCCUAAAAAUGCCAGCUUCUUUGGACUUAGAAGAUGACCUGGAUAAAUGAUAAAAAUUAAGAAAGAGAUUUUGAAGUUUUCUUAUUGUCCUCUUGGCAUAUGCUUCUGGAAUAAUAUUCACCAUGGUUUUGGAUGACCUUCCAAACUUAGAAGACAUCUAUACUUCCUUGUGUUCAUCAACAAUGGAAGACUCAGAGAUGGAUUUUGACUCUGGACUAGAAGAUGAUGACACAAAAAGUGAUAGUAUUUUGGAGGAUUCCACAAUUUUUGUGGCCUUCAAAGGAAAUAUAGAUGAUAAAGACUUCAAAUGGAAAUUAGAUGCAAUAUUGAAAAACGUGCCCAAUUUGUUACACAUGGAGUCCAGCAAGCUAAAAGUACAGAAGGUGGAGCCCUGGAACAGCGUGCGUGUGACAUUCAACAUCCCCCGGGAAGCAGCGGAGCGGCUACGGAUCCUUGCUCAGAGCAACAACCAGCAGCUUCGGGAUUUAGGGAUUCUCUCCGUUCAGAUUGAAGGGGAAGGUGCUAUUAACCUGGCUUUGGCUCAGAACCGAAGCCAAGAUGUGAGAAUGAAUGGACCCAUGGGAGCUGGAAAUUCAGUUAGGAUGGAGGCGGGAUUUCCUAUGGCAAGUGGUCCAGGGAUCUUUUUUCUAGGAAUAAUAAGGAUGAACAACCCUGCCACUGUUAUGAUACCCCCGGGUGGAAAUGUGUCAUCUUCCAUGAUGGCACCAGGCCCCAAUCCAGAGCUGCAGCCCAGGACUCCUCGCCCUGCUUCUCAGUCAGAUGCAAUGGAUCCACUCCUCUCUGGGCUCCAUAUACAGCAGCAAAGUCAUCCCUCAGGAUCUUUAGCUCCCCCACAUCACCCAAUGCAGCCUGUCUCUGUGAACAGACAAAUGAACCCAGCUAAUUUUCCCCAGCUGCAGCAGCAGCAGCAACAACAACAACAGCAGCAGCAGCAGCAGCAGCAGCAACAACAGCAACAGCAGCAACAACAGUUGCAGGCAAGACCCCCACAGCAACAUCAGCAGCAACAGCCACAGGGAAUUCGACCCCAGUUUACUGCCCCAACUCAGGUGCCUGUUCCUCCAGGCUGGAACCAGCUGCCUUCUGGAGCCCUUCAACCUCCUCCAGCCCAGGGUUCUCUGGGCACAAUGACUGCAAACCAAGGGUGGAAGAAGGCUCCCUUGCCCGGCCCAAUGCAACAGCAACUCCAGGCAAGACCAUCCUUAGCCACGGUACAGACGCCUUCCCACCCUCCCCCUCCAUAUCCCUUUGGCAGCCAGCAAGCCUCACAAGCCCACACAAACUUUCCUCAGAUGAGCAACCCAGGCCAGUUCACAGCUCCUCAGAUGAAGAGUUUGCAGGGAGGGCCCUCUAGGGUCCCAACUCCCUUGCAGCAGCCCCACCUCACCAACAAGUCUCCUGCCUCCUCACCCUCCUCCUUCCAGCAGGGAUCCCCUGCAUCCUCCCCAACGGUUAACCAAACUCAGCAGCAGAUGGGACCAAGGCCACCUCAAAAUAACCCACUUCCCCAGGGAUUUCAGCAGCCUGUCAGCUCUCCGGGUCGGAAUCCUAUGGUUCAACAGGGAAAUGUGCCACCUAACUUCAUGGUGAUGCAGCAGCAACCACCAAACCAGGGGCCACAGAGUUUACAUCCAGGCCUAGGAGAGAAAAGUGAGCCCUCAAACCUUGCUGUGGCGUGGCCUCAGAUCACAUUUAGGGAGCAGAUUGCCAUCUUUUCCUUGGCAUGUUCUAAGUCAGGACAGGCCAAUCCGAACUUUAUGCAAGGUCAGGUGCCUUCGACCACAGCAACCACCCCUGGGAAUUCAGGAGCCCCUCAGCUGCAAGCAAAUCAAAAUGUCCAGCAUGCAGGUGGUCAAGGAGCUGGUCCUCCUCAAAACCAGAUGCAGGUGUCCCACGGGCCGCCAAAUAUGAUGCAGCCCAGCCUCAUGGGAAUUCAUGGCAACAUGAACAAUCAGCAGGCUGGUACUUCUGGGGUUCCUCAAGUGAACCUCAGCAACAUGCAAGGCCAGCCCCAGCAGGGCCCACCAUCUCAGCUGAUGGGCAUGCACCAGCAAAUCGUGCCCUCCCAGGGCCAGAUGGUCCAGCAACAAGGAACCUUGAACCCUCAGAACCCUAUGAUCCUUUCAAGGGCCCAGCUUAUGCCACAGGGCCAGAUGAUGGUGAACCCCCCGAGCCAAAAUCUUGGGCCCUCGCCCCAAAGGAUGACCCCACCCAAGCAGAUGCUUUCCCAGCAGGGCCCACAAAUGAUGGCGCCACAUAACCAGAUGAUGGGGCCUCAGGGGCAGGUUUUGCUCCAACAGAACCCAAUGAUAGAGCAGAUUAUGACCAAUCAAAUGCAGGGGAAUAAGCAGCAGUUUAACACUCAGAACCAGUCCAAUGUCAUGCCGGGACCAGCCCAGAUAAUGAGGGGACCAACUCCAAACAUGCAAGGAAAUAUGGUGCAGUUUACGGGACAGAUGUCAGGACAGAUGCUGCCCCAGCAAGGGCCUGUGAACAACAGUCCAUCUCAGGUUAUGGGCAUUCAGGGACAGGUCCUGCGGCCACCAGGGCCCAGCCCACACAUGGCCCAGCAGCAUGGUGAUCCUGCUACUACAGCAAAUAACGAUGUCAGUUUAUCUCAGAUGAUGCCUGAUGUUAGCAUUCAACAAACCAACAUGGUCCCCCCUCAUGUGCAGGCCAUGCAGGGAAACAGUGCCUCGGGAAACCACUUCUCAGGCCAUGGGAUGUCUUUCAAUGCACCUUUCAGUGGAGCUCCCAAUGGAAAUCAGAUGUCCUGUGGUCAAAAUCCAGGCUUCCCAGUCAAUAAGGAUGUCACGCUAACGAGCCCAUUGUUGGUCAACUUAUUGCAGAGUGACAUAUCUGCAGGCCAUUUUGGGGUAAACAAUAAGCAAAAUAAUACCAACGCAAAUAAACCGAAGAAGAAGAAACCCCCUCGGAAGAAGAAAAAUAGUCAGCAAGAUCUAAACACCCCAGAUACUCGCCCAGCUGGUCUGGAAGAGGCUGAUCAGCCACCGUUGCCUGGAGAACAAGGAAUUAACUUGGAUAACUCAGGCCCUAAACUGCCAGAAUUUUCAAACCGGCCACCAGGUUAUCCUUCUCAACCAGUUGAACAGAGGCCACUUCAGCAGAUGCCUCCUCAACUCAUGCAGCAUGUGGCACCCCCACCACAGCCACCACAGCAGCAGCCACAGCCACAACUGCCUCAGCAGCAGCAGCCACCACCUCCCAGUCAGCCACAGUCUCAGCAGCAGCAGCAGCAGCAGCAACAAAUGAUGAUGAUGCUCAUGAUGCAGCAGGAUCCCAAAUCAGUUAGGCUUCCAGUCUCUCAAAAUGUCCAUCCUCCAAGGGGCCCCCUGAACCCCGACUCCCAGAGAAUGCCCAUGCAACAGAGUGGCAGUGUGCCUGUCAUGGUCAGUCUGCAAGGACCUGCCUCCGUGCCACCAUCACCUGAUAAACAAAGAAUGCCAAUGCCUGUGAAUACUCCCUUGGGAAGCAAUUCAAGGAAAAUGGUCUAUCAGGAGAGCCCGCAGAAUCCUUCCAGCUCGCCACUGGCGGAGAUGGCCUCACUCCCUGAAGCAAGUGGCAGUGAAGCACCAUCUGUCCCAGGAGGCCCAAACAACAUGCCUUCACAUGUAGUACUUCCCCAGAAUCAGUUAAUGAUGACAGGGCCAAAACCUGGACCAUCGCCCCUUUCAGCAACUCAAGGUGCAACUCCCCAGCAACCCCCUGUAAAUUCCCUGCCCAGCUCUCACGGCCACCACUUCCCAAAUGUGGCUGCGCCAACCCAGACAUCUAGGCCCAAAACACCAAACAGAGCCAGCCCCAGACCCUAUUAUCCUCAGACACCCAACAACCGCCCUCCCAGCACAGAACCUUCAGAAAUCAGUCUGUCACCAGAAAGACUCAAUGCCUCCAUAGCAGGACUCUUCCCUCCACAGAUUAAUAUUCCUUUACCUCCUAGGCCAAAUUUAAACAGGGGCUUUGAUCAACAAGGCCUAAAUCCAACAACUUUGAAGGCCAUCGGGCAAGCACCUUCAAAUCUUACCAUGAAUCCUUCCAAUUUUGCUACCCCACAAACUCACAAAUUAGAUUCUGUGGUAGUGAAUUCUGGAAAGCAGUCUAAUUCUGGAGCAACAAAACGGGCAAGUCCAAGCAACAGUCGCAGGUCUAGUCCUGGGUCCAGUAGGAAAACCACUCCAAGCCCUGGGAGGCAAAAUUCAAAAGCCCCUAAACUUACUCUGGCCUCUCAGACAAAUGCAGCCCUAUUGCAGAAUGUGGAGUUGCCGAGAAAUGUAUUGGUCAGUCCCACUCCUCUGGCCAAUCCCCCUGUACCUGGGAGCUUUCCUAACAACAGUGGGCUGAAUCCUCAGAAUUCUACUGUGUCUGUGGCUGCAGUUGGGGGUGUUGUUGAGGAUAACAAGGAGAGCUUGAAUGUGCCUCAGGACAGUGAUUGCCAGAAUUCCCAGAGUAGGAAGGAACAGGUAAACAUUGAACUAAAAGCAGUCCCUGCCCAAGAAGUUAAAAUGGUUGUCCCUGAAGAUCAGUCCAAAAAGGAUGGGCAGCCUUCGGAUCCUAACAAACUUCCCAGUGUCGAAGAGAACAAAAAUUUGGUGUCUCCUGCUAUGAGGGAAGCACCAACAUCGUUAAGUCAACUUCUUGACAACUCUGGAGCUCCCAAUGUGACAAUUAAACCCCCUGGGCUUACAGAUCUGGAAGUAACACCUCCAGUAGUUUCUGGGGAGGACCUCAAAAAAGCAUCUGUCAUUCCCACACUGCAGGAUCUGUCUUCUUCUAAAGAACCUUCUAAUUCCCUAAACUUACCUCACAGUAAUGAGCUGUGUUCAUCCCUUGUGCAUCCCGAAUUGAGUGAGGUCAGUUCUAACGUUGCACCAAGCAUCCCUCCAGUAAUGUCAAGACCUGUUAGCUCUUCCUCCAUUUCCACUCCCUUGCCCCCAAAUCAAAUAACUGUAUUUGUCACUUCCAAUCCCAUCACAACUUCAGCUAACACAUCAGCAGCUUUGCCAACUCACUUGCAGUCUGCAUUGAUGUCAACAGUUGUCACAAUGCCCAAUGCGGGUAGCAAGGUUAUGGUUUCUGAGGGACAGUCAGCUGCUCAGUCUAAUGCCCGGCCUCAGUUCAUUACACCUGUCUUUAUCAAUUCAUCCUCAAUAAUUCAGGUUAUGAAAGGAUCACAGCCAAGCACAAUUCCUGCAGCCCCACUGACAACCAACUCUGGCCUGAUGCCUCCCUCUGUUGCAGUUGUUGGCCCUUUACACAUACCUCAGAACAUAAAAUUUUCUUCUGCUCCUGUACCGCCUAAUGCCCUCUCCAGUAGUCCUGCUCCAAACAUCCAGACAGGUCGACCUUUGGUCCUUAGCUCACGAGCCACCCCUGUUCAGCUUCCUUCCCCUCCUUGUACGUCUUCUCCAGUUGUCCCUUCUCAUCCCCCUGUGCAGCAAGUGAAAGAAUUGAAUCCAGAUGAGGCUAGCCCUCAGGUGAACACCUCAGCAGAUCAGAACACUCUUCCCUCUUCACAGUCAACCACAAUGGUUUCUCCCCUUUUGACCAAUAGUCCAGGGUCCUCUGGCAACCGGCGAAGCCCAGUCUCGUCUAGUAAGGGCAAAGGAAAAGUGGACAAAAUUGGCCAAAUUUUGUUGACCAAGGCAUGUAAGAAAGUUACAGGCUCUCUUGAGAAAGGGGAAGAACAAUAUGGUGCAGAUGGAGAGACUGAAGGCCAAGGGCUAGACACCACAGCUCCGGGGCUCAUGGGAACAGAGCAGUUAUCCACAGAGCUGGACAGUAAAACCCCAACGCCCCCAGCACCCACUCUGCUAAAAAUGACCUCUAGCCCUGUGGGCCCGGGCACUGCCUCAGCAGGACCCAGCUUACCUGGCGGUGCUCUCCCCACCAGUGUACGCUCGAUAGUAACCACUCUGGUACCCUCCGAGCUCAUCUCCGCCGUACCGACCACAAAAAGCAAUCAUGGUGGCAUAGCAUCUGAGUCACUUGCGGGUGGCCUAGUGGAGGAGAAGGUGGGAUCCCAUCCAGAACUUCUACCCAGCAUAGCCCCGUCGCAGAAUUUAGUCUCAAAGGAAACUUCAACCACAGCACUGCAGGCCUCUGUUGCCAGACCAGAGCUGGAGGUAAAUGCUGCCAUAGUCUCUGGACAAAGCAGUGAGCCCAAAGAGAUAGUUGAAAAGUCCAAAAUCCCAGGCCGAAGAAACUCCCGAACUGAAGAGCCAACUGUGGCCUCUGAAAGUGUGGAAAAUGGACAUCGUAAACGAUCUUCUCGACCUGCUUCAGCCUCCAGCUCUACUAAAGACAUAACCAGUGCGGUGCAAUCCAAGCGAAGAAAAUCCAAGUAAACAAGCAGGACUGCGACUUGAUACUUGGAAAUGUGUGUGACUUUUACAAAGAGCAAUUUUGAGCUGUGACUUUUUUAAAUCAAUUUCUGUACAGUUAGUAAUUUUAAUAAUGUGGCCCUUUUCCUAGUCCCUGCAACCUGUUUCAUAAAGUGCAAUGGGGAAAGCAGGACUGUUGAGCCCUUUUGGUGUUGCGAGUUGAAGUUCAAGGUUUCUAAAAUGUUGUCUUGUAUUGAAAGGAGCUAAUGCCAUUAUAAAUGUUACUAGUUUUCACAUUUCCUAAGCAGCCUAGAGUACAGGGUGAGCAUUUUUAGAUCUCCUAAUGAUGUAUUGUGCCGUGGAAGUACUGUGUGUGAAUAGCAGUAGUGGGGGCAAAAGCAAUCUUCUCAUUUGGAAAUGUUGUAAAUAAUUUUAUUAUAUAGUGUUUUGGAUGUAUUUGUUGUAGAAAUGGACCAGUGAAUAAAGAGAAUCUAAGGAUUUGUACAAUGUGAAAUAACGUGUUAAAUAAAUGUCAUUGUCAUAGAACAUAAAGUUAUGUUAUUGGUAAGGGA